ACUCCACACCUGGCUGGAGCAGGAAAUGCCGAGCGGCGCCUGAGCCCCAGGGAAGCAGGCUAGGAUGUGAGAGACACAGUCACCUGCAGCCUAAUUACUCAAAAGCUGUCCCCAGGUCACAGAAGGGAGAGGACAUUUCCCACUGAAUCUGUCUGAAGGACACUAAGCCCCACAGCUCAACACAACCAGGAGAGAAAGCGCUGAGGACGCCACCCAAGCGCCCAGCAAUGGCCCUGCCUGGAGAACAUCCAGGCUCAGUGAGGAAGGGUCCAGAAGGGAAUGCUUGCCGACUCGUUGGAGAACAAUGAAAAGGAGGAAACUGUGACUGAACCUCAAACCCCAAACCAGCCCGAGGAGAACCACAUUCUCCCAGGGACCCAGGGCGGGCCGUGACCCCUGCGGCGGAGAAGCCUUGGAUAUUUCCACUUCAGAAGCCUACUGGGGAAGGCUGAGGGGUCCCAGCUCCCCACGCUGGCUGCUGUGCAGAUGCUGGACGACAGAGCCAGGAUGGAGGCCGCCAAGAAGGAGAAGGUAGAGCAGAUCCUGGCAGAGUUCCAGCUGCAGGAGGAGGACCUGAAGAAGGUGAUGAGACGGAUGCAGAAGGAGAUGGACCGCGGCCUGAGGCUGGAGACCCAUGAAGAGGCCAGUGUGAAGAUGCUGCCCACCUACGUGCGCUCCACCCCAGAAGGCUCAGAAGUCGGGGACUUCCUCUCCCUGGACCUGGGUGGCACUAACUUCAGGGUGAUGCUGGUGAAGGUGGGAGAAGGUGAGGAGGGGCAGUGGAGCGUGAAGACCAAACACCAGAUGUACUCCAUCCCCGAGGACGCCAUGACCGGCACUGCUGAGAUGCUCUUCGACUACAUCUCUGAGUGCAUCUCCGACUUCCUGGACAAGCAUCAGAUGAAACACAAGAAGCUGCCCCUGGGCUUCACCUUCUCCUUUCCUGUGAGGCACGAAGACAUCGAUAAGGGCAUCCUUCUCAACUGGACCAAGGGCUUCAAGGCCUCAGGAGCAGAAGGGAACAAUGUCGUGGGGCUUCUGCGAGACGCUAUCAAACGGAGAGGGGACUUUGAAAUGGAUGUGGUGGCAAUGGUGAAUGACACGGUGGCCACGAUGAUCUCCUGCUACUACGAAGACCAUCAGUGCGAGGUCGGCAUGAUCGUGGGCACGGGCUGCAAUGCCUGCUACAUGGAGGAGAUGCAGAAUGUGGAGCUGGUGGAGGGGGACGAGGGCCGCAUGUGCGUCAAUACCGAGUGGGGCGCCUUCGGGGACUCCGGCGAGCUGGACGAGUUCCUGCUGGAGUAUGACCGCCUGGUGGACGAGAGCUCUGCAAACCCCGGUCAGCAGCUGUAUGAGAAGCUCAUAGGUGGCAAGUACAUGGGCGAGCUGGUGCGGCUUGUGCUGCUCAGGCUCGUGGACGAAAACCUGCUCUUCCACGGGGAGGCCUCCGAGCAGCUGCGCACACGCGGAGCCUUCGAGACGCGCUUCGUGUCGCAGGUGGAGAGCGACACGGGCGACCGCAAGCAGAUCUACAACAUCCUGAGCACGCUGGGGCUGCGACCCUCGACCACCGACUGCGACAUCGUGCGCCGCGCCUGCGAGAGCGUGUCUACGCGCGCUGCGCACAUGUGCUCGGCGGGGCUGGCGGGCGUCAUCAACCGCAUGCGCGAGAGCCGCAGCGAGGACGUAAUGCGCAUCACUGUGGGCGUGGAUGGCUCCGUGUACAAGCUGCACCCCAGCUUCAAGGAGCGGUUCCAUGCCAGCGUGCGCAGGCUGACGCCCAGCUGCGAGAUCACCUUCAUCGAGUCGGAGGAGGGCAGUGGCCGGGGCGCGGCCCUGGUCUCGGCGGUGGCCUGACUGUGGGGACAAUCUAUAAAGAGUCUGCGUCACAUGCAUGAAGACACUUCAGUAUCUCGGCAAUGCCCUCCAGACAGCUCCUCCAGCCAUCUGUGCCAAGGGGAGUGUGAGGAGUGACAGACCAGGCUGUAGGAACAGGAAUGGGGUGUCAUGGGGGAUGGCAGAGCAGUGGACAGUACACUGCCUGGCCCGGGCCCCUGCUUGCCUGCCCAUGGAAUGUGUGCAGAGGGAGUGCCAGGCCAGGUGCUGCUCUGGAGAAGUGGGGGAAUGAGGCUGGUCCUGCUGCAGGUCAGUCUCAGCACCGUCCUGUCCAGUCAGAGUCACUUAGGUUUGCCAGUGAGUAGGGGCCCAGAUACAUGUUGGAUUUCUAAGGUCCCUCCAGAUGCUCCUGUCAGUGGAACGCCUAUUUAGAGUUAGCCAAGCGUAGGCAUAAUGCCAUCUUUCUGCAGCAUAAAAUACAGUGACAUAGAAACAUAUUUGUGUGAUUUUCAUGCAUUCCUUUUUUGAUGAGAGAUAUUACCCAGCUAAUUAGGAACAACUGUUUUGUUUCCUUCAGAUCAUAACCCAAAGUUGUGAUUUUGAAAAGUCAUGUCCCCCUUCAGAUUUCUUGUUUUCUGCUACUUCUCAUGUGGAAUUGCUUUGGCUCUUCUUAGUUCUCUUGAGUCUAAAUUAUUCCUUAUAAGUUGGUGCAAGCAUCUGAUUAUUUUGUUAUCAUUACUGUUAUGCUCAAGCAUUCACAGAGUGGAACACAUUUUAAUAUCAAUUGCUUUCUAUUUCUCCUUUAUAUUACAGUUCAGGACAUUGUAUUAAUUAUUAAAAUUCUAUUCGUAGGUAGGUUAUAUGACUGAAUUGAAAUAGAUAAAAUGAAUUUCUUUUCUAGAUAACAAAGGAGGUGUCAUAAAACACUUGUUAUGGGCCAGUGUGAUGGCUCAUGCCUAUAAUCUCAGUGCUUUGAGAGGCUGAGGUGGAGGAUUGCUUGAGGCCAGGAAUUUGAGACCAGCCUGGGGCAACAUAGCAAGACC